AAAGAAAUGCGUGGGACAGAAUGGCGGGUCCAUCCUGGACGGGAUGGGGCCCCUGACCCCUGUGUGCCUGCGCUCUGCCAGCUCCUGCGCAGAGCAGGUACUCGGGGGAGGGAGGAUGGUUUGCUCCAAACUCAGGUCCCAACUGGUGUCUGACUUGGCCGCAGAAUCCUUUGGGUCCUGGUUUCUUCAUACAUGCAAUAUUGGGGGUUUGGCCUUGGGGGUCUCUUCCAGCUGAGUCCACUUCUGUCCCCAGCCUGUAAACUGUCUGCACCUAUUGACUCUUGAUGGUCUCUGAGGGACUCAACUUUAGGAACUCUGUCCGUUUUGUGCUGCUGUCACAGAGUGCUUGAGACUGGGUAAUUUAUAAUGAACAAUCAACUGGCUCACGGUACUGGACAGGUGCCAGCAUCUGGCGAGGGCCGUCCAGCUGCGUCAUCACAUGGUGGAAGGCAGGAGGGGAGCCACCCCACCCUUUUAUAACCAAUCCCAGCCGUUAGGGCGCAGCCUUCAUGGCCUAACCACCCUCUGAAGGUCCCACUCGAUACUGUUAAAAGGCAAUGAAAUUUCAACAGGUUUUGGAGGGGACAAACAUUCAAACCAUGGCAGAAAGUGUGGAAGGAGCAAUAACCACACUGAACAGAAUGACCAUGGUAAUUAAACCCCAAGUGAAACCAUGACCUGUUUUACAUCAUCCUGGAGAGAACAGUGCAGCUCCAGUACUUGCUGAGCUGCAGAGACAGGGUCCAUCCAACUCGACAGCAUCCAGCAGCCACUCCAGGCCGCCAGCAGACAGAUGUUGGGAGCAGCACUGAUAGUUUGGGUUUUCGUUUGUUUUUUUAAGACAGGGUCUCACUUGCCCAGGCUGGAGUGCAGUGGUGUGAUUAUGGCUCACUGCAGCCUGGAACUCGGGCUCAAGCGAUCCUCCCACCUCAGCCUCCUGAGUAGCUGGGACUACAGGUGUGUGCCACCAAAUCCAGCUAAUUUUUGUUACUUUUUGUAGAGAUGGGGUCUCACUAUGUUGCCCAGGCUAAUAGAUUUUUUUAAAUGAUCAUACAGGACGGCUGGGUGCAGUGGUUCACGCCUGUAAUCCCAGCACUUUGGGAAUCCCAGUACUUUGGGAGGCCGAGGCGGGCAAAUCACCUGAGGUCAGGAGUUUGAGACCAGCCUGACCAACAUGGAGAAACCCCGUCUCUACUAAAAGUACAAAAUUAGCCGGGCGUGGUGGCGCAUGUCUGUAAUCCCAGCUACUCGGGAAGCUGAGGCAGGAGAAUCGCUUGAACCCAGGAAGCGGAGGUUGCAGUGAGCCGAGAUCGCGCCACUGCACUCCAACCUGGGCAACAAUACAAGACUCCAUCUGAAAAAAAAAAGAUCACACAGGAAAACAGAAGUUCGAUUUUACGUCGUACACUGCUGUAAUUUCAGCACAUGUGGACUCGUGUAACCAACACCAUAACCUUCCAUCACCCCUGAAACUCCCUCCCGCCAGCCCUUUAGGGUUGCCCCUCCCCCCGAACCCCACCAGCCCCUGGUGACCACUGAUCUGUCCUCCAACCCAUAGUGUUUUUCCGGGAAUGUCACAAAAACAGAAGCCGACCAUGGGUCACCUUUCUGGCGCCUUUCUCCCCGCACAAAGUCUUUGUCCUUGUGAAGUUGUCACGUGCCAAACGCUUGUCCCUUUUUCCUGCUGGGUAAUACUCCCGGUGCCGCCCUUGCUGUUCGUCGAUGCACAUCUGGCUGCUUUUCGCUGGCUGCGAGCGGAGCUGCUAGGGACAUGGCCACGGGGCUGUGAGAGCGGAGUUUCCUCUCUCCGGUGACCCUGAGCUGCGCCUUUCUCAGCCGCCUCCCGAGGCCCCAGGCGCUCUGCGGGGGCUCUGGCGGGGUUGGUGGGGGUGGGCGUUCUCGUUGUUUCAGCGGCGCUGCCCCAGGCCCUGCGGGAGGGACCGUGGGACCCGAGACAUCCCCGCCUGGCCUCCGCUCCCCACCCGGGAGUGGGGCUCGCACCCCCCCAACCUCGGGUAAAGACGCUUCUGGAAGGAAGGGCGCCCCGCGGACCCCGCCCAACCCUGCCCAGCCCAGCCCAGCCCAGCCCAGCCCUUCCCGGGGCGGCGGCGCGGGAAGCAGGCGGCGGCGCACGGGCGUCGUCAUGGCAACCCCACCGGCUCCGGGGGCCGGGACCGCUGCCCCCUCCGCCCCUCGACCCCCGCCCCCCCGCCCUUCCUGGCUGCGGCUGGACCCGGCUGCGCGGGGCGCGAGGCUGCCUUUCCCGGGAUCACCAGGGACCACCCGGCGCGCUCCCCGGGAAUCCGCACCCCUGGCCCCAGCGCUCCGGAGCGACCCGGGUCAGCCCCUGGCUGCCUGCAAUGGGCCCCCGGGCGAACCCCGGGCGGACCCAGGAGUGAGCACCCGGUGCGCGGCAACGAUGAUCCCGCAAGGGAAGCUCACGGGAGGCAGGAGCUGUGGCAGCCGCCCCAGGAUGGGGCGCGGGGAGCGCGCUGAGCUGUCCUUUCCCGCAGCGGCCCCGCGGUUGAAGCGUGGGCUUGGGUUUUGGUUUUUCUUCUGUGGCAACAGUUCUGUUGAGAUAUUACUCGCCUGCCAUACAACUCACCCAUUUUAAAAGUACACCUCAGGGGUCCUGCGUGUAUUGACAAACCCGCCGCCGUCACCACAGCCAAUUUCAGAACAUUUUCAUCUCUUCAAAAGAAACCCUGUACCCUUCAGCUGUCACCCUCCUGGUCCCCAUCCGGUCCUCGUCCCGCCCUCAGCAGCCACGCACUGCCUGUAAAGUCCCCUGUCCUGCCCUGUAGGUGGAAUCUAUACCUUGGGGUCUGUUCUGACGUUCACCUAACAGCCUUUCCAGGCUCAGCUGUGCUAUUGUAUGGACCAGGGGGUUGUUUUGUUUUUGUUGUUUGUUGAUUGUGUGUGUGUGUGUGUGUGUGUGUGUGUGUGUGUGUGUGAGCCUGGCGUGGUUGCGGGCGCCUAUAAUCCCAGCUGCUCAGGAGGCUGAGGCAGGAGGAUCACUCGAGCUCAGGAGUUUGAGGCUGCAGAGUUGAUCAUGCCACUGGACUCCAUCCUGGGCGACAGAGCAAGACUCUGUCUUUUAAAAAAAAAAACGGGGCUGGGCGCGGUGGCUCACGCCCGUAAUCCCAACACUUUGGGAGGCCGAGGCAGGCGAAUCACGAGGUCAGGAUUUCGAGGCCAGCCUGGCCAACAUGGUGAAACCCCGUCUCUACUAAAAAUACAAAAAUUAGCUGGGCAUGGUGGCGGGCGCCUGUAAUCCCAGCUACUAGGGAGGCUGAGCCAAGAGAAUGGCUUGAAUCCGGGAGGCGGAGGCAGAGGUUGCAGUGAGCCGAGAUCGUGCCACUGCACUCCAGACUGCAGCCCUGGUGACAGUGCGAGACUCUGUCUCCAAAAAAAAAAAAAAAACAAACAAAAAACAAUAAAUAACAAGGUCGGCUGAGGUGGCUCACGUCUGUAAUCCUAGCACUUUGGGAGGCCGAGGCGGGUGGAUUACCUGAGAUCAGGAGUUUGAGACCAGCCUGACCAGCAUGGAGAAACCCCGUUUCUACUAAAAAUACAAAAUUAGCCAGGCGUGGUGGCGCAUGCCUGUAGUCCCAGCUACUCGGGAGGCUGAGGCAGGAGAAUCGCUUGAACCUGGGAGGCAGAGGUUGCAGUGAGCCGAGAUCAUGCCAUUGCACUUGCAGCCUGGGUGACAGAGCAAGACUCUGUCUCAAAAAAAAAAAAAAAAAAAGACUCAAAAAAAAACAAAAAUCAGCCAGGCGUGGUGGUGUACACCUGUAGUCCCAGCUACUCUGGAGGCUGAGGCAGGAGAAUCGCUUGAACCCAUGAGGCAGAGGUUGCAGUGAGCCGAGAUUGCGCCACUGCACUCCAGCCUGGCAACAGAGCAAGACUCCGUCUCAUAUAAAGAAAUAAAACAAAAAUAAACAAAUUUUAAAAACAAACACAUUCCUAUACAGGUUUCUGUGUGGACAGCGUCUGCUCUUGGGUCUGCACCUGGGAGUGGAAUUGCUGGGUUGUGUGGUAACUGGAUGUUCACCCAUAGGAUGAACGACCACACUCUUUUGCACAGUGGCCGAUGGUUCUGGUCUCUCUACAGCCUCACCAACUCUUAUAUUCUUUUUGAUUACAGCCACUCUAGCAGGCAUGAGGUGGUACGUCAUUGUGGCUUUGACCUGCAUUUCUCUGGUGUCUAAUGGUGUUGAGCAUUUUUUCGUGGGUGUUACUGACCAUUUGUAUAUCUUAGAGAAAUGUCUAUUCAGAUAAUUUGCCUAUUUUUAAUUGGGUUCGUUGUCUUUUUAUUGAGUUGUAAUACUUUAUUCGGGAUACUAGACCCUUAUUAGACACAUGAUUUGCAAAUAUUUUCACCCAUUCUUUGGGAUGUCUUGUUAACCUUUUUGAUGGUGUCCCUUGAAGCACAAAAGUUUUUAAUUUUGAUGAAAUCUAAUUUAUUUUUGUUGUUGUUCCUUGUGCUUUUGGUGUCAUAGCUAAGGAACCCCUGCUUAAUCCAAGAUCAUGAAGAUUUGUGUCUAUGAUUUCUUAACAGUUUUAUAGUUUAUUUAUAUUUAUAUAAAUAUGUUUUUGAGACAGGGUCUCACUCUGUUGGCGAGGCUGGUCUUGAACUCCUGACCUCAGGUGAUCUGCCUGGCUCAGCCUCCCAAAGUGCUGGGAUUGCAGCCGUGAGCCACCGCGCCCGGCUUGACUUCUUCCUUUUAUAUGUGGGUAUUUUUCUGUCCCAGCGUCAUUUGUUAAAAAGACAGUCCUUUCUCCGUGUAAUUGUUUUGGCACCGUGUGGAAACCCGCUGCCUGUAGCCAGGAGCUUCUUUCCAGCCCUCAGUUCUGUCCCAUUGCUCUGUGUGUCUAUUCUUACGUCCUCAUGGCAGCCUUGUAGUAAGCUUUGAAAUUGGGAAGUGUGAGUUCUCCAACUUUGUUCUUCUUUUUCAAGAUUGUUUUGGCUAUUCUGGGACCCUCAAAUUUCCAUGUGAAUUUUUAGGAUAAGCUUUUCAGUUUCUGCGGAGGAGCCAAGUGAGAUGUUGAUAGGAGUUGCGUAGAAUCUGUGGAUGUGUUUGGAGAGUGCCGCCGUCUCCGCUACAUUAAGUCCAGAUCCGUGGAUUGAGGGUGCCUUUCCAUUUAUUUUGGUCUUCUUUACUUUCUUUCAACCAAGUUUUGUAGUUUUCAGAGUAUAAAUUUUAUACUUGUUUUGUUCAGCCUAUUACUGUUUUAUUUUUGGUGCUAUUGUAAAUGAAAUCUUCUUAAUUUCAAUUUCAGAUUAUUCACUUAAAUAUACAGAAAUACAGCUGAUUUUGUAUAUUGAGCUUGUCUCCUGCAAUGUUGCUGAACUUGUUUAUUAGGGUUUUUUUAAGUGAAAUCCUUAGGACUUUUUAUAUACAAGAUGAGGUCACUUGUAAAGAGAGAUAGUUUACCUCUUAAUUUCCAACCUGGAUGCCUUUAAUUUCAUUUCCUUCUCUAAGUGCCUGGUUAAAGCUUCAGUACAAUGUUGAUUAGAAGUGGGUAUCUUAGGCUGGGCGCGGUGGCUAACACCUGUAAUCCCAGCACUUUGGGAGGCCGAGGCGGGAGGAUCACGAGGUCAGGAGAUCGAGACCAUCCUGGCUAACAAGGUGAAACCCCGUCUCUACUAAAAAUACAAAAAUUAGCCGGGCGUGGUGGCGGGCACCUGUAGUCCCAGCUACUCGGGAGGCUGAGGCAGAAGAAUGGCGUGAACCCGGGAGGCAUGGUGGUGCAUGCCUAUAGUCCUAGCUACUUGGGAGGUUGAGGUGGGAGGAUCAUUUCAGCCCAGAAAACGGAGGCUGCAGUAAGCCAUGAUCGUGCCACUGCACUCCAGCCUGGGAGACAGAGCAAGACCCUGUCUCAAAAAAAGAAAAACUGUUCUGAAGCACAGUGUAGUCUAGUACUGUGGCAUUCCCACCUGUAUUCCUGCUUGUUCCAUUUACUUGAGAAACAUUUUUUUCAUAAAUAAUAUGAAAACAUAUCCAUCCCAGUUUCUGUACAUUAAUUCCAGACUAAGAGCAUUUAACCUGAGUUUAGUGGUAGAUUUAAGGACACUCAUGAGAAAAACCUCCAUUUAUACAAGAGGAACAGGACCCUUCCUUAUCUCGAGGAUGAUGUCCCGCAGGAGACGCCUGCUCUCCUCCAGACAGGCUCUAGGGCUGUUCAUCUGACCUGCCUUGGAAUGUCUCACGUGGCUGCGACGCCAGCCUUUCAAUCGUCUCCCAUGGAUGAAGCCAUCGUGGGUGUGUCUUUGGUAUGUGUCUCUGUUGCUUGGUCUGCCCUCUUUUUUUUGAGACGGAGCCUCACUCUGUCACCCAGGCUGGAGUGCAAUGGCCCAAUCUCAGCUCACUGUAACCUCCGCCUCCUGGGUUCAAGCGAUUCUCCUGCCUCAGCCUCCCAAGUAGCUGGGAUUACAGGCAUGCGCCACCACACGCAGCUAACUUUUGUGUUUUUAGCAGAGGCGGGGGUCUUGCUCUGUUGCCCAGGCUGGUCUCAAACUCCUAGGCUCAAGCAAUCUGCCCACCUUGGCCUCCCAAAGUGCUGGGAUUACAGGUGUGAGCGACUGCGCCUGGUCCAGGAAGGGAACUUUAACACAUAAUGGAUAAAGCUGGACCCUCAAGCAAAAUAGGAAUAUUUAAAAUCCAUUGUUUUGGAUUAACUGCAGCAUCUCCAGAUUAUCUUUCCUCCAUUUUAAAGUUACCUACAAAGGGUCCAUACCUUGAUGGUAGCAUCAGCCCUCCACAGCCCAUCUCUUUCUUUCUUUAUUUUAUUUUUAUUUUUUUGAGACGGAGUCUCGCUCUGUUGCCCAGGCUGGAGUGCAGUGGCUUGAUCUCGGCUCACUGCAACCUCUGCCUCCUGGAUUCAAGCGAUUCUCCUGCCUCAGCCUCCCGGAUAGCUGGGAUUACAGGCGUGUGCCACCACACCUGGCUAAUUUUUGUAUUUUUAGUAGAGACGGGAUUUCACCAUGUUGGCCAGGCUGCUCUCAAACUCCUGACCUCGGAUGAUCCGCCCGUCUCGGCCUCGCAAAGUGCUGGGAGUACAGGCAUGAGCCACCACUCCCGGCCAGCCAGCCCAUCUCUUUCACUGUUACAACUAACAACUCAAAUCCAGGAAAAACAAAGCACCCCCCGCCCCCGCCACCACCGCCCUGCCACUGAGGACUCUGCAAAGUAAACCAGUAAACCAAAGCUGUGGAGGUGGCCCCUGUGGGGAAGCCGUUUCCUGGUUUUAUCUUCCCUUUUCUCUCGUAGCUUUGCCCCAGGAUGGGCCUCAGUUACGGAACUGCACAGAAACACGGAAAGCUAAAACUCCCAUAGAAACCUUGUCCUUUUGGCAAGAGAAAUUGUGAACAGGGGCCACUGAGGUCCAGAAAGCGUGUGGUGGGGGAAUCCCAGAAGGGAGCGAGUGGGAGAAAGAGGCCUUGGGACUCUGAGGAGGAACCAGCAGCAGCCCCGGCUCCCCCACCCGAGCUGCACCUGUGUGGGGUGCACUCAGAGAAGCAACAGGAAUUGGCUUUGAAAGUGGAACCUCGACUGGAGCAGAGGCAGCAGAACUUUGUGGUUGGAACUAACCAGGUUGAUGGGCAUUUAAAAAAAAAAAAAAUCAACAUUCUCCAGCGGAUUGUUGCGGAGUCCACCCAGCAUAACCGUCAAAAUGUCCAGUUCAUGGCCGGGCGUGGUGCCCACAGCUGUGAUCCCAGCACUUUGAGAGGCGGAGGCGGGCAAAUCGCUUGAGCCCAGGAGUUCGAGACCAGCCUGGGUAACCUGACAAAAAUCAGUUUCUACCAAAAAAUACAAAAAUAAGCUGGGCGUGGUGGCAUGUGCCUGUAUUCCCGCUACUUGGGAGGCUGAGGUGGAAGGAUUGCUUGAGCCUGGUAUGCAGAGGUUGUAGUGAGCUGAGAUUGCACCACUGCACUCCAGCCUGGGUGACAGAGCCAGACCUGGUCUCAAAAUUUUUUUAAAAAGCCCAAUUCAUAAUCCCAAAUUAUGUGACAUAUAAAAAAUCAUGAGAAUGUGACCAGUUUCCAAAGGAAAAGUGAUACAGUUUGGAUAUUUUUCCUGCCCAAAUCCCAUGUUGAAUUGUAAUCCCCAGUGCUGGAGGUGGGGCCUGGUAGGAGGUGACUGGAUCAUGGGAACGGGUCUCUCAUGAAUGGCUUGGGCCACCCCCUUGGUGAUAAGUGAAUUCUUGCUCUGAGUUUACAUGAGAUCUGGUCAUUUCAAAGUGUGUGGCACCUCUUCCCUGCUCCUCCUCUGCCUUCCACCAUGAUUGGAAGCUUCCUGAGGCCUCCUCAGAAGCAGAUGCUGCGAUGCUUCCUGUACAGCUGUAGAACCAUGAGCCAGUUAAACUUAUUUUUCUUAUAAAUUAUCCAGUCUUAGAUAUUUCUCUUUUUUUUUUUUUUUUUUGAAACAGUCUCGCUCUGUUGCCCGGGCUGGAGUGCAGUGGCCUGAUCUCGGCUCACUGCAAGUUCCACCUCCUGGGUUCACGCCAUUCUCCUGCCUCAGCCUCCCAACUAGCUGGGAUUACAGGCACCUGCCACCACGCCCAGCGAAUUUUUUGUAUUUUUAGUAGAGACAGGGUUUCAUUGUAUUAGCCAAGAUGGUCUCAAUCUCCUGACCUCGUGAUCCGCCUGCCUCAGCCUCCCAAAGUGCUGGGAUUACAGGCGUGAGCCACCGUGCCUGGUUGCUUAGCUAUUUAUAGCAAUUGCACGAAUGGCCUAAUACAGAAAAUUGGUACCAAGGAGUAAAGCAUUGCUAUAGAUACCUGAAAAUGUGGAAGCAGCUUUGGACCUGGGUAAUGGGCAGAGGUUGGAAGAGUGUGGAGGGCUCAGAAGGAGACAGGAUGAUGAGGAAGAAGAAUUUGAUGAGGAAGAAUUUGGAGCUUCUUAGAAACUGGUUAAAUGAUUGUGACCAAAAUGUUCAUAGUGUUGUGGACAGUAGAGGCCAGGUUGACGAGGUAUCAGCUGGAAAUGAGGAACUGAUUGGAAACUGGAACAAAGGUCAUGUGUUCUUUGCUAAGGUUUUGGCAGAGAGCAUGGCUGUAUUCUGUUCAUGCCUCGGGAUCCAUGGACAUUUAAACUUGAGAGUCAUGAGUUAGGGUAUCUGGUGGAAGAAAUCCCUAAGCAGCAAAAUGUUCAAAAAGUGGCAUGGCUGCUUCUAACAAACUGUACUUAGAUGAGGGAGCAAAGGAAUGACUUAAAGUUGGAACUUAUAUUUAAAAGAGAAGCAGAGUGUAAAAGUUUGGAAAAUUGGCUGGGUGUGGUGGCUCACACUUGUAAUCCCAGCACUUUGGGAGGCCAAAGCAGAUAGAUACCGUGACGCCAGGAGUUCAAGACCAGCCUGGCCAACAUGGCAAAACCUCAUCUCUACUGUUGGGAAUAACGCUCAAAAUCCUAAGGUGAUCGAACACUCAAACAAAGGAUUCUUUUUUGUUGUUCUGUUUUGUUUUUGUUUUCGAGAUGGAGUCUUGCUCUGUCACCCAGGCUGGAGUGCAGUGGCACUAUCUCGGCUCACUACAAGCUCCACCUCCUGGGUUCAUACCUCAGCCUCCCAAGUAGAUGGGACUACAGACACCCGCCACCAUGCCUGGCUAAUUUUUUGUAUUUUCAGUAGAGACAGGGUUUCACCGUGUUAGCCAGGAUGGUCUUGAUCUCCUGACCUCAUGAUCCGCCCACCUCAGCCUCCCAAAGUGCUGGGAUUACAGGCGUGAGCCACCGCGCCCAGCCUCAAACAAAGGAUUCUUAGCAAAGCAAUUUUACUUCUGCGUAGACAGGUGCUUCUCCUUGGCCAGUUGCCAUGAGAGCACACCUGAACAAAGGGGCAUGAGGGCCUUUAUUUCUGAUGCAAGUCCUGUCCCUGUACCCUUUCCCCAUUGGCCAGGGUUGGGUUGCACAAACUGAACUAAUCCCAGUUGGGUAGACAUUUGAACUUUCUUUAGAUAUGGUGGGCAUGUAAGGGAGAGAGGGAAAGAAGAAGGGGAAGGAGCGUUUGCAAUGAGCUAGAGACUAGUCUCCUUUCCAAAUAAGGAAAGGAAUGUGAGCUGGUACUGAUAAGCCUGGUCCUGUGGCGUGUCCAGGCAUCUAACAAAGGCAGAAAAGAGAAAAAGGAAAAAGGGGUGGGGGAGGUACUAUGAAUUAAGGAAGAAAGGAUUGAUCAGGCUAUUUGAAGAGAAACCUCAUCAUAUCCCACAUCUACUAAAACUACAAAAAUGAGCCGGGUGUGGUGGAGGGCACCUGUAAUCCCAGCUACUCGGGAGGCUGAGGCAGGAAAAUCACUUGAACCUGGGAGGCGGAGGUUGCAGUGAACCAAGAUCACACCACUGCACUCCAGUCUGGCGACAGAAUGAGACUUUGUCCGCCACGCAAAAAAAAAAAAAAAGUUUGGAAAAUGCGCAGCCUGGCCAUGUGGCAGAGAAAGGAAAAGCUUUUUCAGGAGAGGAAUUCAAGCAGAGUGUGGAGGAACCACUUCUUAGAGAUAUUUGCGUGUUUGAAAAUGAGCCGAGAGGUGAUGACCAAGCCAAUGGAAUGAUGACCUUCAUGACAGCCCCUCCCAUCACAGGCCCUGAGGCCUAGGGGAACGAAAUGGUUUUGUGGGCCAGGCCCAGGGCCCCACUUCCCUAUACAGCCUCAGGGCAGUGCUCCCCAUAUGGCAUCCCAGCAGCUCCAGCUCCAGCCUCAGCUCACAGGGGCCCAGGUACAGCUCAGGCUGCCACUUUGGAGGUUGCAAGCUGUAAGCCUUGACAGCUUUCACAUGGCAUUAAGCCUGUGGGUGCGCAGAAUGCAAGAGUGAAGGCUUGGCAGCCUCUGUCUCGAUUUCAGAGGAUGUAUGAGAAAGCCCAAGUUCCCAGGCAGAUGCCUGCUGCGGGGGGCAGAGCCCCCACAGAGAACCUUUACUAGGGCAGUGCCAAGGAGCAAUGUCCACAAAUCCCCAAAAUCCCAUCUGACUAAUUGAGAGAGUUGGAGCCCCCACACAGAGUCCCCGCUGGGGCACUGCCUAGUGGAGUUGCGAGAAGGGGCCACUGCCCUCCAGAAUUCAGAACGGCAAAGUCAUCAGCAGCUUGCACCCUGCGGUUUCACAAGCACUCAACAACCUGUGAGAGCAGCGUUAGGGAUGGAACCUGCAAAGCCCCGAGGGCGGAGCUGCCCAAGGCCUUGGGAGCCCACCCCUGGCACCAGUGUGCCCUGGAUGUGGAGCAUGGAGUCAAAGGAGAUUGUUUUGGAGCUUUCAGAUUUAACACCUGCCCUGCUGGGUUUGGAACUUCCAUGGGACCUGUAGUCCCUUUCAUUUGGCUGAUUUCUUCCUUUUGGAAUGACAGUACUUACCCAGUGCCUAUAUUCCUAUUGUGUCUUGGAAGUAAAUUACUUGUAUUUUGUUUUACAGUCUCAUUGGUGGAAGGGACAUGCCUUGUCUCGGGGGAGACUUUGGACUUUUGAGUUAACGCUGGAAUCAGUUAAGAUUUUGGGGGAUUCUUGGGAAGGCAUGAUAGUAUUUUGCAAUGUAGGAAGGACGUGAGAUUUGGGAGGGGUCCCGGGUGGAAUGAUAUAGUUUGGAUAUUUGUCCUCACCCAAAUCUCAUGUUGAAUUGUAAUCUCCAGUGUUGGAGGUGGGGCCUGGUGGGAGGUGUUUGGGUCAUGGGAGCUUGGGCCAUCCCUUGGUGAUAAGUGAGCUGUCUCUCUGAGUUCACACGAGAUCUGGUCAUUUACAAGUGUGUGGCACCUCCCCCAUCCCCCCACUUGCUCCUGCCUUUGCCAUGUGAUGUCCCUCCUCCUGCUUUGCCUUUGACCAUGAUUGGAAGCCUCCUGGGGCCUCUCCAGAAGCAGAUGCCGCUGUGCUUCCUGUACAGCCUGCUGAACCACGAACCAAUAAGCCUUUCUUUAUAAAUGA